ACUUAUAUAAGGGAUAAUUUUUCUUUUUUUUUUUUUUUUGAGACGGAGUCUCACUCUUCCGCCCAGGCUGCAGUGCAGUGGCAUGAUCUUGGCUUACUGCAACCUCCGCCUCCUGGGUUCAAGCAAUUCUGUGGCUUCAGCCUCCGGAGUAGCUGGGAUUACAGGCACAUGCCACCACACCCAGUGAAUUUUUGUAUUUUUAGUAGAGACGGGGUUUCACCAUGUUGGCCAGGCUGGUCUUGAAUUCCUGACCUCAGGUGAUCUGCCCACCUCAGCCUCCCAAAGUGCUGGGAUUACAGGCGUGAGCCACCACACCAGGCCCGAGAAAUGCUUUUUUAAAAAACACACAUCUUAUGGCAUUCACCUUCUUGGAGCUCUAGGACAGUGGUUCUCAAAAUUUUUUUCUCUCAGGACCUCUUAAAAAUCAUCAAGGACCCCAAAAAGCUUUUGGGUAUGUGGGUUAUAGCUAUCAAUAUUUAUGGUACUAGAACUUAAAAGUGAGAAAAAUUUAAAACACGAGAAUACAUAGGCACACAUUCUAUUCAUCGUGGGAACCAUGGUGUCAAUACAUAUCAUGUAGCUUCUGAAAAACUCCACUGUACACUUAUAGAAUGAAGAAGGCAAAAAACUUUUUUUUUUUUUUUUUUGAGACGGAGUCUCGCUCUGUCGCCCAGGCUGGAGUGCAGUGGCGCGAUCUCGGCUCACUGCAAGCUCCGCCUCUCGGGUUCACGCCAUUCUCCUGCCUCAGCCUCCCAAGUAGCUCGGACUACAGGCGUCCUCCACCAUGCCUGGCUAAUAUUUUGUAUUUUUUAGUAGAGACGGGGUUUCACCGUGUUAGCCAGGAUGGUCUCGAUCUCCUAACCUGGUGAUCCGCCCGCCUCGGCCUCCCAAAGUAUUGGGAUUACCCGCGUGAGCCACCGCGCCCGGCUGCAAAUAAUCUUUCUUUUUUUCUGAGACAGAGUCUCGCUCUGUUGCCCAGGCUGGAGUGCAGUGGCACGAUCUCGGCUCACGGCACGCUCCGCCUCCCGGGUUCACGCCAUUCUCCUGCCUCAGCUUCCCGAGUAGCUGGGACUACAGGGGCCCGCCACCACGCCCGGCUAACUUUUUGUGUUUUUAGUAGAGACGGGGUUUCACCGUGUUAGCCAGGAUGGUCUCGAUCUCCUGACCUUGUGAUCUGCCCGCCUCGGCCUCCCAAAGUGCUGGGAUUACAGGCGUGAGCCACCGCGCCCGGCGGCGAAACACGAUAUUGUACUAACAUCUUAAUUUUGUUAUAAAAUCUCACAAACCCCCUGACAUAGUCUCAGAGAUCUGUAGGGCCGAGGUUACAUUUGGAGAACCCGUACUCUAGGGCCAAAUCCAUUCUUCUUGCCCUGGCUCACUUGUCCCCCCCACCGCCCCGCGCUGGAGCCACUGCCUAGUUCUUCAGCCCUAGAUGGUGCUCGCCAGACCUCCUCUCAAUGCUCAUCACACACAGGGCUAUUCCUUUCCUCCAAUGAACCAAACGCCUCCCGCCCACCUCCAGGUCCCAGUCCUCUGUUCCCUUUGCCUGGUCCACCCUUGCCCUCCCUGGGUCGCAGACGAGGUCGGCCUCGUCAUUCCCCGCAGACCGCCGCGCGUCCCUCUUGUGCGGUUCACCACAGUUGUAUUUAAGUGAUCGUGUGAGUCGUCGUUAAAUGCCUGUCUCCCCGCGGAUCAUGGGCUCCUCGAGGACAGGGACUGGCCUGUCUGUCCACUGCUGUAACCCCGCGCCGGCAUAGGGACCUAAGGCCCACUGGAGGGCGCUCAUCAAGUAGCUGCUGGAUGUUGACGAAGGAAGCGGCGGCGCAGCUCAGGGAUCUCCGAGUCAGGACGGUCGGCCAGACCCACGGGGUAACGGGUCUAAUCGUGUAGGAAUAAAGCUGUAUUCCAGUGCUUCCAAACGGUUCUCUCAUUCCAACCCCUUUCCAAGCUCAAUGAAUAUUCCAAUCACCUCUGGUCCCUUCCAGUGACCCUGAACCGCUCAGAGAACGCCCCGUCGACACCGUUCGGGGCGGGCGCCACUACUGGCGCAUGAGAUGCGCUCAAGCAGAGGGUACUCCACCAGCGAGGAUACACCGAGCCGACGGGGAUCUCGGUCUCGGCGCCGGAAGCCUCUGAGAGCCGAAUCUGGAACCGGAUGUGGCUGCUUCCUGCCCCGCCCCCUGCCGAGGGGGCGGGAAUCGAGGGCCCUUCGGAAAACCCGGCCGGGAUUUCGGCCCCUGUGUCCGUCUGGGAUGAGGAGGAGGAUGGUGCCGUGUUUACCGUCACAAGCCGCCAAUAUCGACCUCUUGAUCCCUUGGUCCCUAUGCCUCCCCCACGUUCCUCCCGACGGCUCCGAGCUGGCACUCUGGAGGCCCUGGUCAGACACCUACUGGAUACCCGGACAUCAGGGACUGAUGUGAGCUUCAUGUCAGCCUUCCUGGCUACCCACCGGGCCUUCACCUCCACGCCUGCCUUGCUAGGGCUUAUGGCUGACAGGCUGGAAGCCCUUGAAUCUCAUCCUACCGACGAACUAGAGAGGACAACAGAGGUAGCCAUCUCUGUACUGUCAACCUGGCUGGCCUCUCACCCUGAGGAUUUUGGCUCUGAGGCCAAGGGUCAGCUUGACCGGCUUGAGAGCUUCUUACUUCAGACAGGGUAUGCAGCAGGGAAGGGUGUUGGGGGGGGCAGCGCUGACCUCAUCCGCAAUCUCCGGUCCCGGGUGGACCCCCAGGCCCCCGACCUUCCUAAGCCCCUGGCCCUCCCCGGCGAUCCCCCUGCUGACCCCACGGAUGUCCUGGUGUUCCUCGCUGACCACUUGGCCGAACAGCUGACCCUGCUAGAUGCGGAACUUUUUCUCAAUUUGAUCCCCUCUCAGUGCCUGGGAGGCCUGUGGGGUCACAGAGACCGGCCAGGACAUUCUCACCUCUGCCCAUCUGUCCGAGCUACUGUCACACAGUUUAACAAGGUGGCAGGGGCAGUGGUUAGUUCUGUCCUGGGGGCUACUUCCACUGGAGAGGGACCUGGGGAGGUGACCAUACGGCCACUCCGUCCCCCACAGAGGGCCCGGCUCCUGGAGAAGUGGAUCCGCGUGGCAGAGGAGUGCCGGCUGCUCCGAAACUUCUCUUCAGUUUAUGCCGUGGUGUCAGCCCUGCAGUCCAGCCCCAUCCACAGGCUUCGGGCAGCCUGGGGGGAAGCAACCAGGGACAGCCUCAGAGUCUUUUCCAGCCUCUGCCAGAUUUUCUCCGAGGAGGAUAAUUAUUCCCAGAGUCGGGAGCUGCUCGUGCAGGAGGUGAAGCUGCAGUCUCCUCUGGAGCCACACUCCAAGAAGGCCCCGAGGUCUGGCUCCCGGGGUGGGGGUGUGGUCCCAUACCUUGGCACCUUCCUGAAGGACCUUGUGAUGCUGGAUGCAGCCUCCAAGGAUGAGUUGGAGAAUGGAUACAUCAAUUUUGACAAGCGGAGGAAGGAGUUUGCAGUCCUUUCUGAGUUGCGACGGCUCCAGAAUGAAUGUCGUGGCUAUAACCUCCAACCUGACCAUGAUAUCCAGAGGUGGCUACAGGGGCUCCGGCCACUGACAGAGGCUCAGAGCCAUCGUGUAUCCUGUGAGGUGGAGCCACCUGGUUCCAGUGACCCUCCUGCCCCACGGGUGCUUCGGCCAACAUUGGUCAUCUCGCAGUGGACAGAGGUUUUGGGCUCUGUUGGGGUCCCUACCCCGCUUGUGUCCUGUGACCGGCCCAGUACUGGGGGAGAUGAGGCGCCUACAACUCCUGCUCCUCUGCUGACUCGGCUGGCCCAGCACAUGAAGUGGCCAUCUGUCUCGUCACUAGACUCUGCCUUGGAAAGCAGUCCAUCCCUGCACAGUCCAGCUGACCCCAGCCACCUCUCCCCACCAGCCUCCUCCCCUAGGCCUUCUCGAGGUCACCGCCGCUCAGCCUCCUGUGGCUCCCCGCUGAGUGGGGGUGCAGAAGAGGCCUCCGGGGGGACUGGAUAUGGGGGAGAGGGAUCUGGGCCAGGGGCCUCUGAUUGCCGUAUCAUCCGAGUCCAGAUGGAGUUGGGGGAAGAUGGCAGUGUCUAUAAGAGCAUUUUGGUGACAAGCCAGGACAAGGCUCCAAGUGUCAUCAGUCGUGUCCUUAAGAAAAACAAUCGUGACUCUGCAGUGGCUUCAGAGUAUGAGCUGGUACAGCUGCUACCAGGGGAGCGAGAGCUGACUAUCCCAGCCUCGGCUAAUGUAUUCUACGCCAUGGAUGGAGCUUCACACGAUUUCCUCCUGCGGCAGCGGCGAAGGUCCUCUACUGCUACACCUGGCGUCACCAGUGGCCCGUCUGCCUCAGGAACUCCUCCGAGUGAGGGAGGAGGGGGCUCCUUUCCCAGGAUCAAGGCCACAGGGAGGAAGAUUGCACGGGCACUGUUCUGAGGAGGAAGCCCCGUUGGCUUACAGAAGUCAUGGUGUUCAUACCAGAUGUGGGUAGCCAUCCUGAAUGGUGGCAAUUAUAUCACAUUGAGACAGAAAUUCAGAAAGGGAGCCAGCCACCCUGGGGCAGUGAAGUGCCACUGGUUUACCAGACAGCUGAGAAAUCCAGCCCUGUGGGAACUGGUGUCUUAUAACCAAGUUGGAUACCUGUGUAUAGCUUCCCACCUUCCAUGAGUGCAGCACACAGGUAGUGCUGGAAAAACGCAUCAGUUUCUGAUUCUUGGCCAUAUCCUAACAUGCAAGGGCCAAGCAAAGGCUUCAAGGCUCUGAGCCCCAGGGCAGAGGGGAAUGGCAAAAUGUAGGUCCUCGCAGGAGCUCUUCUUCCCACUCUGGGGGUUUCUAUCACUGUGACAACACUAAGAUAAUAAACCAAAACACUACCUGAAUUCUA